AUGUCCAGCUGGGCUGUGGGGAAUCUUCCAGGCCUGUUACCUGUAUGCUGCCUGGUGACACCUGGUGGAUUUCACGGGGACUGCCAUGGCACCUACGGAGUACAGUCCGGCCCUGACAGUCAACAGGUUGAGAAGCCUGAUCUAGCUGUGGCAGGGAAGACAGAUACCAGAGAAACUAACAAUGAAAACGGACUCGUUGAUGGAGGAAAAGUUGGAAUGCAGCCUCUGGUGCUGUUUGAGCGAUCCCUCUACCCCGGGUCGCUGCUGUGUUCUGGAAAGGCGCAUUGUACCCUGGAUGCGGCAGAAACUGUAAAGGAGGAUGUGGCUAUAGGGGCUGAUUGUUCUCAUGAGUGUUACUACUCUUCUUUCCCACAGUUAAAAGAAUAUUGGCAGAGGAAGAGCCCUGGCAUUCCAGAAGGAGCUAACAGGAAAAAGAAAAUCAAUGGCAGUAGCCCUGACACAGCCACUUCUGGUGGUUACCACUCACCUGGGGAUUCAGCAACAGGUAUCUACGGGGAGGGCCGUGCAUCAUCUGCUACCCUGGAGGAUCUGGAGAGCCAGUACCAAGAACUAGCAGUGGCCCUGGAUUCAAGCUCCACAAUAAUCAGUCAACUCACUGAAAACAUCAAUUCACUGGUAAGAGUCCAGUGGGGUCCCCUGAUUCCAGCCUGUGAAUCCUGGACUCCAGUUUCCUCUUGGGGCCCUGAAGAAAGGGGCUAGGAGCCCCUGAUGCCAAGGGCAAAUGGGGAGCUGGGCACCCAGGUCUCACCUGGAGGGACCCCAGAGCACAGAACAUGCAGCAUGGCUCUUCUGCACUGCCCUCUUUGCUGACUCUCUCUUCUCCAGACACCCCUGCUCUAGUCCUUGCCACACAUGCCCUGGGGUUGUCACCUCUCAGGAAAGCACUAGCCUGACUGGUUUUCAGGGGCCCGUAUUUCUGCCCUGCCUCAGUCCCUAAUUUGCUUUUUGAGUCUGGACAAGCCAUCUCUCCUCCUUAGGCUCGUGUUUCUGGAGGAGGUAGAGAGUAUCAAAGGUCACUGUUAGCUCAGAGAUUUAAAGGCUCCUAGAAUGGAAACCUCAGGACCAAGGGCUCCUGUCUGUCCUUUGCUGUCUUAUAUCUCUGCUAUGAAGAACUGUACCUGGCCUGUACGUGCUCAGUAAAUGUUUGUUGAGUGAAUGCACCUUUCUCAAUCGUAAGCUGGCAGAAGGGGGGUGGGCCUUUCUCAAACUCUGUCUCUAGAGGUUCAGCAGCCCCUCUCUGCAGGGCCCUUUCCCCUCUGCUUUAGGCAGGUUCACACAUUGAAAGAGGAGAAGCAUGAGAUACAUCAGGUACAGAAGCUUGGGAGGAACUUGUUCAAACUCAAAAACCAGACGGGUAAGAUGGGGCUGCCAUGACCUAGGAGCAGGACUGGCAUCAGAGGGCUGUGAGGGUGACUUAGAAUGCCCCGGGGAGGUGGGUAGAUGGAAGGGCUUUGAGGCAGAGGGAAAGAGGUCUGUGCCAGGAGAUGGCAAGUCUUGUCAUCUCCAUGAGCCUCAGUGUCCCUCUCAGUAAAGAGGGAGGAGUGCCCGUUGUCAGCCACCCACAGUGCUAUCUGAAAGUGACUUGGAAGAUUGGCUACCAUCCGGGUGUGAGGAGUCAUUAGCAGUGAGGCCAAGUUUGGGAAGCCUGAGAGGAGGAGCUGUGCACCGAAGGGAGGAUUUUUU